AGCUUCCGCCGCCGCGUCGUUUCAGGACCCGGACGGCGGAUUCGCGCUGCCUCCGCCGCCGCGGGGCAGCCGGGGGGCAGGGAGCCCAGCGAGGGGCGCGCGUGGGCGCGGCCAUGGGACUGCGCCGGAUCCGGUGACAGCAGGGAGCCAAGCGGCCCGGGCCCUGAGCGCGUCUUCUCCGGGGGGCCUCGCCCUCCUGCUCGCGGGGCCGGGGCUCCUGCUCCGGUUGCUGGCGCUGUUGCUGGCUGUGGCGGCGGCCAGGAUCAUGUCGGGUCGCCGCUGCGCCGGCGGGGGAGCGGCCUGCGCGAGCGCCGCGGCCGAGGCCGUGGAGCCGGCCGCCCGAGAGCUGUUCGAGGCGUGCCGCAACGGGGACGUGGAACGAGUCAAGAGGCUGGUGACGCCUGAGAAGGUGAACAGCCGCGACACGGCGGGCAGGAAAUCCACCCCGCUGCACUUCGCCGCAGGUAACCGGGGCCAGCGUCCCCUCGCCUCGCUCCAGACCCCACCUGCGCAGCCGGGGCCCACAGGUUUUGGGCGGAAAGACGUAGUUGAAUAUUUGCUUCAGAAUGGUGCAAAUGUCCAAGCACGUGAUGAUGGGGGCCUUAUUCCUCUUCAUAAUGCAUGCUCUUUUGGUCAUGCUGAAGUAGUCAAUCUCCUUUUGCGACAUGGUGCAGACCCCAAUGCUCGAGAUAAUUGGAAUUAUACUCCUCUCCAUGAAGCUGCAAUUAAAGGAAAGAUUGAUGUUUGCAUUGUGCUGUUACAGCAUGGAGCUGAGCCAACCAUCCGAAAUACAGAUGGAAGGACAGCAUUGGAUUUAGCAGAUCCAUCUGCCAAAGCAGUGCUUACUGGUGAAUAUAAGAAAGAUGAACUCUUAGAAAGUGCCAGGAGUGGCAAUGAAGAAAAAAUGAUGGCUCUACUCACACCAUUAAAUGUCAACUGCCACGCAAGUGAUGGCAGAAAGUCAACUCCAUUACAUUUGGCAGCAGGAUAUAACAGAGUAAAGAUUGUACAGCUGUUACUGCAACAUGGAGCUGAUGUCCAUGCUAAAGAUAAAGGUGAUCUGGUACCAUUACACAAUGCCUGUUCUUAUGGUCAUUAUGAAGUAACUGAACUUUUGGUCAAGCAUGGUGCCUGUGUAAAUGCAAUGGACUUGUGGCAAUUCACUCCUCUUCAUGAGGCAGCUUCUAAGAACAGGGUUGAAGUAUGUUCUCUUCUCUUAAGUUAUGGUGCAGACCCAACACUGCUCAAUUGUCACAAUAAAAGUGCUAUAGACUUGGCUCCCACACCACAGUUAAAAGAAAGAUUAGCAUAUGAAUUUAAAGGCCACUCGUUGCUGCAAGCUGCACGAGAAGCUGAUGUUACUCGAAUCAAAAAACAUCUCUCUCUGGAAAUGGUGAAUUUCAAGCAUCCUCAAACACAUGAAACAGCAUUGCAUUGUGCUGCUGCAUCUCCAUAUCCCAAAAGAAAGCAAAUAUGUGAACUGUUGCUAAGAAAAGGAGCAAACAUCAAUGAAAAGACUAAAGAAUUCUUGACUCCUCUGCACGUGGCAUCUGAGAAAGCUCAUAAUGAUGUUGUUGAAGUAGUGGUGAAACAUGAAGCAAAGGUUAAUGCUCUGGAUAAUCUUGGUCAGACUUCUCUACACAGAGCUGCAUAUUGUGGUCAUCUACAAACCUGCCGCCUACUCCUGAGCUAUGGGUGUGAUCCUAACAUUAUAUCCCUUCAGGGCUUUACUGCUUUACAGAUGGGAAAUGAAAAUGUACAGCAACUCCUCCAAGAGGGUAUCUCAUUAGGUAAUUCAGAGGCAGACAGACAAUUGCUGGAAGCUGCAAAGGCUGGAGAUGUCGAAACUGUAAAAAAACUGUGUACUGUUCAGAGUGUCAACUGCAGAGACAUUGAAGGGCGUCAGUCUACACCACUUCAUUUUGCAGCUGGGUAUAACAGAGUGUCCGUGGUGGAAUAUCUGCUACAGCAUGGAGCUGAUGUGCAUGCUAAAGAUAAAGGAGGCCUUGUACCUUUGCACAAUGCAUGUUCUUAUGGACAUUAUGAAGUUGCAGAACUUCUUGUUAAACAUGGAGCAGUAGUUAAUGUAGCUGAUUUAUGGAAAUUUACACCUUUACAUGAAGCAGCAGCAAAAGGAAAAUAUGAAAUUUGCAAACUUCUGCUCCAGCAUGGUGCAGACCCUACAAAAAAAAACAGGGAUGGAAAUACUCCUUUGGAUCUUGUUAAAGAUGGAGAUACAGAUAUUCAAGAUCUGCUUAGGGGAGAUGCAGCUUUGCUAGAUGCUGCCAAGAAGGGUUGUUUAGCCAGAGUGAAGAAGUUGUCUUCUCCUGAUAAUGUAAAUUGCCGCGAUACCCAAGGCAGACAUUCAACACCUUUACAUUUAGCAGCUGGUUAUAAUAAUUUAGAAGUUGCAGAGUAUUUGUUACAACACGGAGCUGAUGUGAAUGCCCAAGACAAAGGAGGACUUAUUCCUUUACAUAAUGCAGCAUCUUACGGGCAUGUAGAUGUAGCAGCUCUACUAAUAAAGUAUAAUGCAUGUGUCAAUGCCACGGACAAAUGGGCUUUCACACCUUUGCACGAAGCAGCCCAAAAGGGACGAACACAGCUUUGUGCUUUGUUGCUAGCCCAUGGAGCUGACCCGACUCUUAAAAAUCAGGAAGGACAAACACCUUUAGAUUUAGUUUCAGCGGAUGAUGUCAGCGCUCUUCUGACAGCAGCCAUGCCCCCAUCUGCUCUGCCCUCUUGUUACAAGCCUCAAGUGCUCAAUGGUGUGAGAAGCCCAGGAGCCACUGCAGAUGCUCUCUCUUCAGGUCCAUCUAGCCCAUCAAGCCUUUCUGCAGCCAGCAGUCUUGACAACUUAUCUGGGAGUUUUUCAGAACUGUCUUCAGUAGUUAGUUCAAGUGGAACAGAGGGUGCUUCCAGUUUGGAGAAAAAGGAGGUUCCAGGAGUAGAUUUUAGCAUAACUCAAUUCGUAAGGAAUCUUGGACUUGAGCACCUAAUGGAUAUAUUUGAGAGAGAACAGAUCACUUUGGAUGUAUUAGUUGAGAUGGGGCACAAGGAGCUGAAGGAGAUUGGAAUCAAUGCUUAUGGACAUAGGCACAAACUAAUUAAAGGAGUCGAGAGACUUAUCUCCGGACAACAAGGUCUUAACCCAUAUUUAACUUUGAACACCUCUGGUAGUGGAACAAUUCUUAUAGAUCUGUCUCCUGAUGAUAAAGAGUUUCAGUCUGUGGAGGAAGAGAUGCAAAGUACAGUUCGAGAGCACAGAGAUGGAGGUCAUGCAGGUGGAAUCUUCAACAGAUACAAUAUUCUCAAGAUUCAGAAGGUUUGUAACAAGAAACUAUGGGAAAGAUACACUCACCGGAGAAAAGAAGUUUCUGAAGAAAACCACAACCAUGCCAAUGAACGAAUGCUAUUUCAUGGGUCUCCUUUUGUGAAUGCAAUUAUCCACAAAGGCUUUGAUGAAAGGCAUGCGUACAUAGGUGGUAUGUUUGGAGCUGGCAUUUAUUUUGCUGAAAACUCUUCCAAAAGCAAUCAAUAUGUAUAUGGAAUUGGAGGAGGUACUGGGUGUCCAGUUCACAAAGACAGAUCUUGUUACAUUUGCCACAGGCAGCUGCUCUUUUGCCGGGUAACCUUGGGAAAGUCUUUCCUGCAGUUCAGUGCAAUGAAAAUGGCACAUUCUCCUCCAGGUCAUCACUCAGUCACUGGUAGGCCCAGUGUAAAUGGCCUAGCAUUAGCUGAAUAUGUUAUUUACAGAGGAGAACAGGCUUAUCCUGAGUAUUUAAUUACUUACCAGAUUAUGAGGCCUGAAGGUAUGGUCGAUGGAUAAAUAGUUAUUUUAAGAAACUAAUUCCACUGAACCUAAAAUCAUCAAAGCAGCAGUGGCCUCUACGUUUUACUCCUUUGCUGAAAAAAAAUCAUCUUGCCCACAGGCCUGUGGCAAAAGGAUAAAAAUGUGAACGAAGUUUAACAUUCUGACUUGAUAAAGCUUUAAUAAUGUACAGUGUUUUCUAAAUAUUUCCUGUUUUUUCAGCACUUUAACAGAUGCCAUUCCAGGUUAAACUGGGUUGUCUGUACUAAAUUAUAAACAGAGUUAACUUGAACCUUUUAUAUGUUAUGCAUUGAUUCUAACAAACUGUAAUGCCCUCAACAGAACUAAUUUUACUAAUACAAUACUGUGUUCUUUAAAACACAGCAUUUACACUGAAUACAAUUUCAUUUGUAAAACUGUAAAUAAGAGCUUUUGUACUAGCCCAGUAUUUAUUUACAUUGCUUUGUAAUAUAAAUCUGUUUUAGAACUGCAGCGGUUUACAAAAUUUUUUCAUAUGUAUUGUUCAUCUAUACUUCAUCUUACAUCGUCAUGAUUGAGUGAUCUUUACAUUUGAUUCCAGAGGCUAUGUUCAGUUGUUAGUUGGGAAAGAUUGAGUUAUCAGAUUUAAUUUGCCGAUGGGAGCCUUUAUCUGUCAUUAGAAAUCUUUCUCAUUUAAGAACUUAUGAAUAUGCUGAAGAUUUAAUUUGUGAUACCUUUGUAUGUAUGAGACACAUUCCAAAGAGCUCUAACUAUGAUAGGUCCUGAUUACUAAAGAAGCUUCUUUACUGGCCUCAAUUUCUAGCUUUCAUGUUGGAAAAUUUUCUGCAGUCCUUCUGUGAAAAUUAGAGCAAAGUGCUCCUGUUUUUUAGAGAAACUAAAUCUUGCUGUUGAACAAUUAUUGUGUUCUUUUCAUGGAACAUAAGUAGGAUGUUACAUUUCCAGGGUGGGAAGGGUAAUCCUAAAUCAUUUCCCAAUCUAUUCUAAUUACCUUAAAUCUAAAGGGGAAAAAAAAAAUCACAAACAGGACUGGGUAGUUUUUUAUCCUAAGUAUAUUUUUUCCUGUUCUUUUUACUUGGUUUUAUUGCUGUAUUUAUAGCCAAUCUAUACAUCAUGGGUAAACUUAACCCAGAACUAUAAAAUGUAGUUGUCUCAGUCCCCUCCAGGCCUCCUGAAUGGGCAAGUGCAGUGAAACAGGUGCUUCUUGCUCCUGGGUUUUCUCUCCAUGAUGUUAUGCCCAAUUGGAAAUAUGCUGUCAGUUUGUGCACCAUAUGGUGACCACGCCUGUGCUCAGUUUGGCAGCUAUAGAAGGAAAUGCUGUCCCAUAAAAUGCCAUUCCUAUUUUCUAAUAUAAAACUCUUUUCCAGGAAGCAUGCUUAAGCAUCUUGUUACAGAGACAUACAUCCAUUAUGGCUUGGCAAUCUCUUUUAUUUGUUGACUCUAGCUCCCUUCAAAGUCGAGGAAAGAUCUUUACUCACUUAAUGAGGACAUUCCCCAUCACUGUCUGUACCAGUUCACCUUUAUUUUACGUUUUAUUCAGUCUGUAAAUUAACUGGCCCUUUGCAGUAACUUGUACAUAAAGUGCUAGAAAAUCAUGUUCCUUGUCCUGAGUAAGAGUUAAUCAGAGUAAAUGCAUUUCUGGAGUUGUUUCUGUGAUGUAAAUUAUGAUCAUUAUUUAAGAAGUCAAAUCCUGAUCUUGAAGUGCUUUUUAUACAGCUCUCUAAUAAUUACAAAUAUCCGAAAGUCAUUUCUUGGAACACAAGUGGAGUAUGCCAAAUUUUAUAUGAAUUUUUCAGAUUAUCUAAGCUUCCAGGUUUUAUAAUUAGAAGAUAAUGAGAGAAUUAAUGGGGUUUAUAUUUACAUUAUCUCUCAACUAUGUAGCCCAUAUUACUCACCCUAUGAGUGAAUCUGGAAUUGCUUUUCAUGUGAAAUCAUUGUGGUCUAUGAGUUUACAAUACUGCAAACUGUGUUAUUUUAUCUAAUCCAUUGCUUAAUGAGUGUGUUUUUCCAUGAAUGAAUAUACCGUGGUUCAUAUGUUAGCAUGGCAGCAUUUUCAGAUAGCUUUUUGUUUGUUGGGAAGUUGGGGUUUUGGGGGGAGGGGGAGUAUUAGUACGUUGCAUGAAAUAGCUUACUUUAUAAUGAUGGAAUUGCUUUUUCUUUUGUCUUGUGAUUUUUUUUUUUGAAGUGAAAUUUAACUUUUUGUGCAAGUAGUACUAUUAUACCCAUCUUCAGUGUCUUACUUGUACUGUAUCACAUUCCAUACCCUCAUUUAAUUCUUAAUAAAACUGUUCACUUGUUUUUCUGGGUAGCAUGGUAAUUACUGGAAUAGUAUAAAUGUGUUGAAUGGUCUUUGAGAAAAUGAAUUAAGAUUACAAUAAACCACAAUUGCAGGAAAACAAUGUAGUUCUGAGUCUAAUAGUGAUAAAGAAUGCAGUUUGAAGUUUGAAAUAUUGAAUAUUGUAGCUGUACUUGCUCAUUAAAAUGAAAGUAGCUGUGA